GCCGCGGCCUUUGUCUCGCAGUCAGGAGGGUGAGCUAGGCCGGCGAGGAGGGGGAGGGGAGGCCAGGCCGGGCCGGGCCGGGCCGGGUGCGGGGGGUCCGGGGAUCUUCCUGAGGCCCUGGCGGGGCGAGUUUCCAGCAGCGCGCGUCUGUGUGGAGUCCGUUUUGCUGCCCGGGGCCUGGGGAAGGCCGUUUCGGGGCUGGCGGGGGCAGGCUUUGCGGGGCAUCCCUAGUCUGAGAGGAGGGCGGGGCCCAACGCCCAGCUGGACAGGAGCUGCUCCGACGGCCCCUGAGGGAACGCGCGCCCCGCCCCUGGCCCCACCUCUGCCCCACACCGGGCACUGGGCCGCCACCUUUGUUGAUGGAAGAGAGAAACUGAGGCAUAGUGCCCAGGGCCAGGGGACCGCAACCACCCGGCCCUUGUCACUGUAGCGUUAAGGCUCAGAGUCUGCGCAGCAGAUAUGUGUCCGCACCCGCCAGGCCUUCAGCUUCCCUCAGACAGGCGGGAAAACCCUAGGCUGCCCUUCUCCGAGCGGAGGGCCGCCCCACACACAGCAGGCGCUUAAACGGAGCAGGGCCAGCCGUUCCUGCCAGAAGCCAGGGCAUGACCCCUGGGGUGCGCGUCUCCACAGACCCGGAGCAAGUGACGUUUGAGGACGUGGUAGUGGGCUUCAGCCAGGAGGAGUGGGGGCAGCUGAAGCCUGCCCAGAGGACCCUGUACCGUGAUGUAAUGCUGGACACCUUCAGGCUUCUGGUCUCUGUGGGACAUUGGUUACCGAAGCCGAAUGUCAUCUCCCUGCUGGAGCAAGAGGCAGAGCUGUGGGCGGUGGAGUCUAGACUUCCCCAAGGCGUGUACCCAGAGAUUAAGGGACAUUUCCAGUUUUUGCUUCUUUCAGACUUGGAAACUAGACCCAAAGUCAAACUGUCAGUUCUAAAGCAAGGCAUCUCUGAAGAAAUAUCCAACAGUGUCAUCUUGGUAGAAAGAUUCCUGUGGGAUGGUCUGUGGUACUGCAGGGGUGAGGACACUGAGGGCCACUGGGAAUGGAGUUGUGAGAGUCUAGAGAGCCUGGCAGUGCCGGUGGCCUUCACGCCUGUGAAGACGCCUGUUCUGGAGCAGUGGCAGAGGAAUGGGUUUGGGGAAAACAUAAGUCUGAACCCUGAUCUCCCACAUCAACCAAUGACUCCUGAAAGACAAAGCCCCCACACAUGGGGAACACGUGGAAAAAGGGAGAAGCCAGACCUAAAUGUUUUACAGAAAACCUGUGUAAAAGAGAAACCCUACAAAUGUCAGGAAUGCGGAAAGGCCUUUAGUCACAGCUCAGCACUUAUCGAACACCACCGGACGCACACAGGAGAGAGACCUUACGAAUGUCACGAAUGCUUAAAAGGCUUCCGGAACAGCUCGGCACUUACCAAACACCAGAGAAUCCAUACUGGGGAGAAACCCUAUAAAUGCACUCAGUGUGGGAGGACCUUCAACCAAAUUGCCCCACUGAUCCAGCACCAGAGAACUCACACAGGUGAGAAGCCCUAUGAAUGCAGCGAAUGUGGGAAAUCCUUCAGUUUUAGGUCCUCCUUCAGCCAGCACGAGCGAACUCACACAGGCGAGAAGCCCUACGAGUGCAGUGAGUGUGGGAAAGCCUUCCGGCAAAGCAUCCACCUCACCCAGCAUCUGCGAAUCCACACUGGGGAGAAACCCUAUCAGUGUGGUGAGUGUGGCAAGGCCUUCAGCCACAGCUCAUCCUUGACCAAACACCAGCGAAUCCACACAGGGGAGAAGCCCUACGAGUGCCAUGAGUGUGGAAAAGCCUUCACCCAGAUCACACCACUGAUUCAGCACCAGAGGACCCACACAGGAGAAAAGCCCUAUGAGUGUGGUGAGUGUGGGAAAGCCUUCAGUCAGAGCACACUCCUGACCGAGCAUCGGAGGAUUCACACAGGAGAGAAGCCCUAUGGAUGCAACGAGUGUGGGAAAACCUUCAGCCACAGCUCCUCACUCAGCCAGCAUGAGCGGACACACACAGGAGAGAAGCCCUAUGAGUGCAGUCAGUGUGGGAAGGCCUUCCGGCAGAGCACACACCUCACCCAACACCAGCGAAUCCACACAGGGGAGAAGCCCUAUGAAUGCAAUGACUGCGGCAAGGCAUUCAGUCACAGCUCGUCCCUCACCAAACAUCAGCGAAUCCACACUGGGGAGAAGCCCUACGAAUGCAACCAGUGUGGCAGAGCCUUCAGCCAGCUUGCUCCCCUCAUUCAGCAUCAGAGGAUCCACACAGGAGAGAAACCCUAUGAAUGUAACCAGUGUGGCAGAGCCUUCAGCCAGAGCUCCCUUCUCAUCGAACACCAGAGGAUUCACACCAAGGAAAAGCCGUAUGGGUGCAAUGAGUGUGGGAAAUCCUUCAGCCACAGCUCCUCGCUCAGCCAGCACGAAAGGACGCACACUGGGGAAAAGCCCUAUGAGUGUCACGAUUGCGGAAAGUCCUUUAGGCAGAGCACCCACCUCACUCAGCACCGGAGGAUCCACACAGGAGAGAAGCCAUAUGCAUGCAGGGACUGUGGAAAGGCCUUUACCCACAGCUCCUCCCUUACCAAGCACCAGAGAACUCACACUGGAUAAACCCACUCCACAUGUGCUGGGGACAUAGGAAGACCUUAAGCCAUAGCUCAUCCCUUUCUAGAUUUGACCCAAUCAUACACAUGAGAAACGUACAUUCAUACACAAGCCUUUUCACACAGCACUCCCCUCAGACACCCUCAGAGAGUUCACACUGAUGGGAAAUGACCAUGGGACCACCAAGCUCUAGGUCAUCCAUCUCUGCAUCCAAAUAGUAGGGAAACGUGGAGAUAAUCAACACUCAGGACCUUCAGCCUUGAACGCCCAUUAGUGCUAUGUUAUAGAACCUACAAAAAAGAAAUGGAACAAAUGUAGUGGAUCCAGGGAACGCUUUUGUCCAAGGAUUCACCGUAUUCCAAACCAGAGAUGUUCAAAUUGGUGAGAAACCCAACAAAUGCCUUUCAUAUAUACGAGAACCAAAUGAAGUCAGAAUUUGCCAUUAUUGCACAUCACAUUUUUGGGGGGGAAAGUGCUUAUGAAUGGUGCAGGUUGACUCUGAUAUUCAUUCCCAAAUGACAGUAUGGCAGAGUGUUCCAGAAAUGAGAGUGGCAUCUUUAUGGAAUCACUGUGGAUACUGACUGUCUCAGUAAACAGCUGUCUUGUCUGUGUGUAUAUUGUUUGAUCAGGGUACAUGGCAGCCAGUCACAGAUUGGAAUUACAUAUGACAAAGUAUCAGUGUACUAUAAACAGGUUUUUAGUUAUCCCUGCAUUAUUUUUGCAAUUAAUCUUUAUAUGCAAUGAGAUUGAAAAGCUUUGUAUGGGAAGACUCAAAAUGUAAAGCUGCUUCCGUAGAGUCUCACUGAUUCUGAGAUGGCUUUUGCUGCUCUGUUCUCCCUCUACAUUUCUCUGCAGAACUCGCGUUAGAAACACAGAUAUUUGUUUUACAAAAAGGGAGAUUUUUCCUUUGUUAAACCAUCGUCUUAUAAGCAAUAGCAAAUUCAUGUUAGAAACUUCUGUUUUGCAAGAUUCAUCUUUUUUGGGAUAUGUUCAAGUUAAUCCUCUCAAACUGCUUUUUCAUUGUUUUCAUACAAUUUAACAUUUUGUUAAACCCUAAGUCCACAAAUAGCAGUCUUUCUGACAACUAUAACCUUUAAAUGGUGACUUGCUGCCCUCAUUAGAAAUUGCAUUGGCUGGCCAGGCGCGGUGACUUAUGCCUGUAAUCCCAGCACUUUGGGAGGCCAAGGUGGGAGGAUCACCUGAGGUCGGGAGAUGGAGGUUGCAGUGAGCUGAGAUCGUACCAUUGCACUCCAGCCUGGGCAACAAGAGUGAAACUCUGUCUCAGAAAAAAAAAAAAAAA